ACUUCCGUUCCACCAUCGCUGCUGGAGCAGCUGCCUUCAGGCCCUGCGCCGCCUCCGGAGUCCAUGGCCGGCACGCGCUGGGUACUCGGGGCGCUGCUCCGGGGCUGCGGCUGUAACUGCAGCAGCUGCCGGCGCACCGGCGCCGCCUGCCUGCCCUUCUACUCCGCCGCUGGCUCUAUCCCGUCGGGCGUCUCGGGCCGCCGCCGCCUGCUGCUGCUGCUCGGGGCCGCCGCGGCCGCUGCCUCCCAGACGCGUGGCCUCCAGACCGGGCCUGUGCCUCCCGGGAGGCUGGCGGGGCCUCCCGCUGUGGCCACCUCUGCCGCGGCCGCGGCCGCCGCGUCCUACUCUGCCCUCCGUGCCUCUCUGCUGCCGCAGUCGCUGGCGGCGGCGGCCGCCGUCCCGACGCGCAGCUACAGCCAGGAGUCCAAAACUACUUACCUGGAAGACCUUCCACCACCCCCUGAGUAUGAAUUGGCCCCGUCCAAGUUAGAAGAGGAAGUGGAUGAUGUCUUUCUCAUUCGAGCUCAAGGACUGCCCUGGUCAUGCACUAUGGAAGAUGUGCUUAACUUUUUUUCAGACUGCAGAAUCCGCAACGGUGAGAAUGGAAUACAUUUUCUCCUAAACAGAGAUGGGAAACGAAGGGGUGAUGCCUUAAUUGAAAUGGAGUCAGAGCAGGAUGUGCAGAAAGCCUUAGAGAAGCACCGCAUGUACAUGGGCCAGCGGUAUGUGGAAGUAUAUGAGAUAAACAAUGAAGAUGUGGAUGCCUUAAUGAAGAGCUUGCAGGUCAAAUCUUCGCCUGUGGUAAAUGAUGGUGUGGUUCGUUUGAGAGGACUUCCUUAUAGUUGCAAUGAGAAAGACAUUGUAGACUUCUUUGCAGGACUGAAUAUAGUUGACAUUACUUUUGUGAUGGACUAUAGAGGGAGGCGAAAAACAGGGGAAGCCUAUGUGCAAUUUGAAGAACCAGAAAUGGCCAACCAAGCCCUGUUGAAACACAGGGAAGAAAUUGGUAAUCGAUACAUCGAGAUAUUUCCAAGCAGAAGGAAUGAAGUUCGAACACAUGUCGGUUCUUAUAAGGGAAAGAAAAUCGCAUCUUUUCCUACUGCUAAGUAUAUAACUGAGCCAGAAAUGGUCUUUGAAGAACAUGAAGUAAAUGAGGAUAUUCAACCCAUGACAGCUUUUGAAAGUGAGAAGGAAAUAGAAUUGCCUAAGGAGGUGCCAGAAAAGCUUCCAGAGGCUGCUGAUUUUGGAACUACGUCUUCUCUGCAUUUUGUCCACAUGAGAGGAUUACCUUUCCAAGCCAAUGCCCAAGACAUUAUAAACUUUUUUGCUCCACUCAAGCCUGUUAGAAUCACCAUGGAAUACAGCUCCAGUGGGAAGGCCACUGGAGAAGCUGAUGUGCACUUUGAGACCCAUGAGGAUGCUGUUGCAGCGAUGCUCAAGGAUCGGUCCCACGUUCAUCAUAGGUAUAUUGAACUGUUCCUGAAUUCAUGUCCAAAAGGAAAAUAAGACUCUAGGGGCUCCAGAUAAUAAGGGUGAAGCAAGAAGCAUUUCAUUUGCACAUCUUUCUUGGACUUGGGAUAUACAGUUCCAGUUUAUUAGCAGCAACUGCUAGGGAAAUGAUUUUGGUGUUUUGGGUUAAUUGCUUCUAAGAAAAGUUUCAUAGUGGACUGUUUAGAAGAAGAAAUGAAAGAUCCAGUUUGGGAUUAUGAAAUAAACCACAAAUUAAAAUUUUUGUUUAAACUGUCCAGGAUCUGAUUUAAAAAUAUGGUCUUUGUUUUAUAUGAUUAAAUGGUUUGUUUUCAUAGAUGAUAUGUUACUCAUUGUAAAGACCACAUAUUUUUAUUCAGCAGUGUUCUUUAAACGGUUUCAUUUAAAAAGUAACUUUUUUUUUUUGCCUGUGAAUUGAGUGCUCUGAUGUAAAACUUCUCAUGGAGUGAAACAGUGAUUUAUUUUAACCAAACAUUCACCAAAGCAAAGAACGGUUUCAGACCUUUGAACUGGUAUGGUUUGGCAGAAUAGUUUUAAAUUUUGCUGUAUUUGAUUACUUAGAGAUAGGAAUUUUUAAAAAUCAAAACAAAAAAUACCACAGCUUAGUGUAAAUGACAAUUUGGCGGUUUUAUGUCUUUAGAAAUGUUUUGCCUUUCUAAGCCUUGUGCUAAAGGCGUAUAACGGUGGUGCCUAUCUACUUAAGGGGGCAUUCUAGUCUUAACUUAAAAGUUGUCUAAACUGUCCCUCCCUGGCUUUUUUUGGUUUGGGGUAGACCUAAGGGUGUUUGUUAGUCUCAAAACUGUGAAGUGACAUGUCAGAACAGUCCAGACUGGUAAGAAAAUUAAUGGCUUCACUUGAAUUUAAACCAGCUCUAGAUAGGAAAAAAAUCAGUCUCCUCAUUUGCUUUUUAAAUGGAGUAGUACAUCCCAUAUUUUAGAACAAGUAGGGGUGCCUUGCUUAAAUAAAAAUAGCAUUUAAUGUAUAAUUGUGUGAAGGGUUUAUGGAUAAAGCUGUACUUCUGUCACAAUGUGGCAGUACUUUCUGCUUUAAUAUUAAACAGCUUGUUAUUUAAAUAUUGGACAAAAUGGCUGGCUUCAAAAUAUAGUCAUUAAUAAACUAACUUUAUGUGCACCUGUGUAGGAGAAUCAAAAUCCUGUAUGCUUUCUUUGCCUUGUUCCUGUUCUCAGGGUGACGACUGCCACCAGGAGAUGCAGUUCUAGUUCUUAAAAUUAAAUUUGCCCAGGUUUCUGACAGGUGAUACCUGGAAGAGAGACUAUGUCUUCUCUUACUUAAUACAUAACCAUCUUUGAUUACCAGCUAAGAUGCGAAAUCACUGUACUGUAGUCAAUAAAUGAAGACUUGUUUCAGGCUGAAGAUUACCUAAGAGUAUUUAUUAUUGGAGUCUGUGAGUCAACUGAAUAUAUUAUUACCUCAAGUCCUGCUAUAUUAAUAUAAGUAGUAAGGGUUAAUUUUCGUGUGUGUGUUCUCUAAAAUCCUGUGAACAUGACUUAACCAGCUUAACAUCAUCAGUAGUACUGCCUAGAUGGAAAUGCGUUUUCAUAUAUGGUUGAAUAUGCCAAGCUAUGAGAACUGGUAUCUGUAGUUGUACGAACUAUUAGAAUGUGAUCUUUGUUGCUCUUUCACAUUUGGUAUCUGAUUUGCUGUGGAAAAGAUCUGUGGGGCCUACUGUGAGGAAUUCAUCUGCAAUUGAUUUAAGCUAAUGAGUUUUAUUUGCACAUCUCUGGAAAAAGAAUGCAAGCAAAGCAUUAAAAUGCUAUAUGAUGGAUGGGUAAGGUUGAAAGGAUAUAUCUUCUUGGCACGCUACAGGCUGAGUUUUCUGUACAAAAUGUGGCCAUUAUUGGGAAAUCAUUUUAUGUAUUUGAAUGCUCCCUUUUGUUUUUGUUCAUGAUCUAGGCUAGUACGUAAGUGAUUGCUAAGGUGGAUGUAGUUAUGGGAAAGGAAGAGAAGCACAUAAUACAGUAAAAGUAAUCUUAUUUCCAUGCAAGUGGAAGACGGUACCGUCUCCCCACAUUUGAGAAGACUGUUUUGCAUCACUCUUUGCUAUUGAAGGAAGCAGUGAUGGUGAAUUUCCUUCUGUUUGGGUUCCUUGUGUCUAUAACUUCCUUUGUGGUAAAGCCAUCAGGAAGAAUAGUGGGAGUGGGGCAUAUGGUCAGGGUGCUCAUAUCCUGCUUUAGCCUAGCUGCUGCUUACGGAGUGCAAGGGAGAACUCUGAGAAGCAGUAUGUAAAUACCAGGGAGCUGAUUGCUGAAUAUUGUGGUCUCAUCUGAAUAUUGUGGUCUCAUCUAAAUAUUGACACCAGGCAAUGAAGCAGAAAUAGAGUAUGUGUCCCUUUAUGCGUGGGUAACUUAAGCUUCUGUCAUGUGGGAAGGGGGACCGAAUCUUCCCUGGGAGGAAGGCUCCAAAUUCUCACUACUUCUGUGUUACUUGAAGGGGGAAGCAUAAGGAACCCAGUUUGAAGGCAACAUUGUGUGCCAUGAAUCUGCUUAUUAAUCAACAUGCCUUGUUAAUGUCCUCUGCCCUGAACAGCCCUUACUCAGUUCUCAUUUGGAAAGUUAUUUUUUGGGGUUACAUCCUGUUUGUUUCAGAAUUUAAAACCCUCCAUGGUGGGUCACUUGAGGUCAGGAGUUCAAGAUUAGCCUGGCCAACUUAGUGAAACUCCGGCUCUACUGAAAAUGCAAAAAUUAGCCAGGUGUGGCACACGCCUGUAAUCCCAGUUACUUGGGAGGCCAAGGCAGGAGAAUCGCUUGAACCUGGGAGGCAGAGGUUGUAGCGAGCCAAGAUCACACCAUUGCACUCCAGCCUGGGCAACAGAGUGAGACUCUGUCAAAAUCAAAAAAACCAAAAUACAAAAAACUCCAUUGUUCUGAGAGUUUCCCCUAAAUUAUCGGAAGACACUCACAUUGAAUUGGUAGGACCUAUAGUAUAGAGGAGAAUGGUAUGUAUGUCAGCAGUAGAGUUCCAAUCCAAAUUGCGCUAUCGCAUUAGAAAUACAUUACCCUCCCACUCCCCAAGUUCAGCAAAUUAGAAGAGAAUCUGAAGUUUGUAGGAAGGGAAUAAAGCUGCUAUAAACAUUUAUGUGCAGGUUUUUGUGUAGACUCGUUUUCAGCUCCUUUGGGUAAAUACCAAGGAACCAGGUUGCUGGAUUGUAAGUUAAGAGUAUGUUUAGUUUUGGAAGAAACUGCCAAACUGUUCCAACAUGACUAUUUUGAAUUCCCAUUGACAAUGAAUAAGAGUUCCUGUAGCUCCUCACCCUCAUUAGUAUUUGGUGAUGUCACUCUUGCAUUUUAGCUAAUGGGUGAAUAGUGGUCUCAUCGUUUUAAUUCCCAAUCCCAUAGUGAUGUGGAGCACCUUUUCAUAUACUUAAUCUGCCAUCCUUAUAUCAUCAUUGGUGAGGUGUCUGGAUUUUCUGUCCAGAAUUUUAGUUCUAGUGGUUUUCUUAUUUUUAGAAAGGAAGUAUAGGAAGGAAGGUUUAAUCUGUCUUAAGCCUGAUUAUAUGAAAAUCAAGAAUAGGCUAGGUGUGGUGGCUGACAUCUGUAAUCCCCGCACUUUGUGAGGCUGAAGUGGGAGGACUGCUUGAGCCUGGGAAGUCAAGCCUGCAGUGAGCCAUGACUGUUGCUGCACUCCAGCCUGAGUGACAGAGUGAGACCCUGUCUCAGAAAAAAAAAAAGCAGGCUCAUUUUAAAGUUGUUUAUAUUUUAUUUUUUGAAGGAAAUAAACUUGAAGAGAUACAAACGGUAGUGAAGAUUCUCCUUCCCCUCCUGUAAUUCAGCUGUUUAGUUUCUAUUCUCGCACAGCCCUGUUAUCAGUUUCUAGUGUAAGCUUGCAGUGACUUUUACUUUAUUUAUAAGCAAGUGUUAGUGGGUGUUGUCAUUUCUUUUAAAAAUAUAAAUUAUACUGUACAUGCUAUUUUGUAUUUUGGCUUUUCUCCCACCUAAACACCCUAAAGAUCAUUUUCUGUCAGUAUAUAAAAUCUUGGUGAUGCCAAUACCCAUCCCUUAGAUUGUACAAGCAGCAUUUUGCCAUGCUUUAUCCCAUAGCCUGCCUCCUGCAGUCUCAUCUUUUUUUCUAUAUGCAUGUCCAAGUAAGUUGUAGACAUUUUUCACUUUUAAUCCUUUCAGCAUACAUGUCAUGGGAAUUUGUUUUUGUUUUUGUUUUUUGUGUUUGAGACAGUCGCUCUGUCACCCAGGCUGGAGUUAUAGUGACGUGAUCCCAGCUCAUUACAGCCUCCACCUCCCAGUUUCAAGCAAUUCUCAUGCCUCAGAUUCCCGAGUAGCUGGGAUUACAGAUGUGCACCACCACGCCUGACUAAUUUUUGUAUUUUUAGUAGAGAUGGGGUUUCAUCAUGUUGGCCAGGCUGGUCUGGAACUCCUGGCCUCCAGUCAUUUGCCUGCCUCGGCCUCCCAAAGUGCUGGGAUUACAGGCAUCAGCCACCACACCCAGCCGUCAUUGGAGUUUUUUUGAGGGAGAUUUGCAGUAAGGUGAAUAAAUGUUAAGUGUAUCAUUUGAUGAGGUUUUUUCUUUUUUUUUUUUUUUUUUUGAGAUGGAGUCUUGUAUCGCCCAGGCUAGAGUGCAGUGGCCUGGUCUUGGCUCACUGCAACCUCCACCUCCUGGGUUCAAGGGAGUCUCCUGCCUCAGCCUCCCGAGUAGCUGGGAUUACAGGUGUGAGCCACCAUACCCAGACUCAUUUGAUGAGUUUUGAUGUAAAAGCAUGUAACUCAAACCCCUAUGUCUGGAACAUCUGUAUUACAUCUGAAUUUUUUCACCUAGUCAAUUCCUGCACCUCUCUCUCCUGUCCCUUCUUCCCUCCCCUGGCAGUCAGCUACUGUUAGGAUUUUGUUCACUGUAGAUUAAUUUUGCCUAUUCUAGAACUUCAUAUAACGGACUCACUUAUGCAGUAUGUAUUCUGUAAGUUCCUUUUACUCAGCAUGUUUGUAUGUUCAUCAGUGUGUUUAAGCUUUGUUCCUUUUUAUGGCUGAGCAGUGUUCUAUGUAUGAAUGCCACAUUUUAACGUUUCACCUGUUAGGUGAACAACUAACUGGUGAACAAUGGGCUGUUUCUAGUUUGGGGCUAUCAUGAAUAAAGUUGGUAUGAACAUGUACAA